GACUUGGGCUUUGAACCCUGAGGGAGGGAGGUGGGAGCCAUGGAGGGCUUCAGACAGAGGGCAGGCCCUGGCUACUGCGGAGAGGACAGAGAAGAAGGAGGAGGGAUGAGGGCAGAAGCCCGGGAACCAGUUAGGACAGUCCAGGUGUGGAAUGCUGGUUGCUUAGUGAUGAGAAGUAAUUGAAUAAUUGUGGACGUGUUUUGGGAGGAACUUGACCGCAGCUGCUGAGCAUCAGGAUACGCAGGGGGUGAGGGCUCCAGAGCAAAGGAGCCACUUCGGUUGCAGCCAGACCCAGGAGGGUCCCUGCCCAGCCCCCACUGCAGGGGGCCCCAGGAUCCCUGGCAGCCCAGCCUGGCCUGUGGUCCUGGGCAGUCCGCUUCCCCCACCCGCUGCUUCCAGUUCCGGGCUUUCCCAGCCGCCUCGCUGUGCUUUCAAAAUCGCCAUCAGCACAGCCCCCUCCUCCGACAGCCCGCCUGCCACUCUCCCCCGGGAGGGCUGCUAGCAGGCACAAGGGAGCCACACUUUUCAUGCUGAGCGCAUUAAAGUGCCGAUAGGAAACGUCUUACAGAUUGUGGAGAGCUGCAGCCAACUCCAGGGUUUCCAGUCUGAGGAGGUCUCACCUGCUGAACCAGCCAGCCCUGGGACGCCCCAGCAGGUGAAGGACAAGACCCUGCAGGAGUCGAGCUUUGAGGACAUCAUGGCCACCAGGUCCUCCGACUGGCUCCGGCGGCCUUUGGGGGAGGACAAUCAGCCGGAGACCCAGCUGUUCUGGGACAAGGAGCCUUGGUUUUGGCACGACACUCUGACCGAGCAACUCUGGCGGAUUUUUGCCGGCGUCCACGAUGAGAAGGCAAAGCCCAGAGACAGACAGCAGGCACCAGGCCUGGGGCAGGAAAGCAAGGCACCAGGAUCCUGUGACCCAGGAACAGACCCAUGUCCUGAAGAUGCCUCCACCCCCAGGCCACCUGAGGCCUCCUCCAGUCCCCCUGAGGGUUCCCAAGACAGGAACACAAGUUGGGGUGUGGUCCAGGAGCCUCCUGGAAGAGCCUCUCGGUUUCUACAGUCCAUAUCCUGGGACCCUGAGGACUUUGAAGAUGCAUGGAAGAGGCCAGAUGCCUUGCCCGGGCAGUCAAAGAGACUCGCCGUCCCGUGCAAACUGGAAAAGAUGCGGAUCUUGGCACACGGGGAGCUCGUGCUCGCCACGGCCAUCAGCAGCUUCACGCGGCACGUGUUCACCUGUGGCAGAAGAGGCAUCAAGGUGUGGAGCCUGACUGGACAGGUGGCUGAGGACAGGUUCCCUGAGAGCCACCUGCCUAUACAGACCCCUGGGGCCUUCCUGCGCACCUGCCUGCUGUCCUCAAACAGCAGGAGCCUGCUCACCGGUGGCUACAACCUGGCCAGCGUGAGCGUGUGGGACCUGGCGGCGCCCUCCCUGCAUGUGAAGGAGCAGUUGCCCUGUGCAGGUCUCAACUGCCAGGCCCUGGAUGCCAACCUGGAUGCCAACCUGGCCUUCGCCAGCUUCACCAGUGGUGUGGUCAGGAUCUGGGACCUGCGGGAUCAGAGUGUGGUCAGGGACCUCAAGGGUUAUCCUGAUGGAGUCAAGAGUAUCGUGGUCAAGGGCUACAACAUCUGGACUGGGGGUCCGGAUGCCUGUCUGCGGUGCUGGGACCAGAGGACCAUCAUGAAACCUCUGGAGUACCAAUUCAAGUCUCAGAUAAUGAGCCUGUCCCACAGCCCCCAGGAGGACUGGGUGCUGCUGGGCAUGGCCAAUGGCCAGCAGUGGCUGCAAAGCACCAGCGGGAGCCAGCGGCACAUGGUGGGGCAAAAAGACAGCGUCAUCCUGAGCGUCAAGUUCUCCCCCUUUGGCCAGUGGUGGGCAAGCGUUGGAAUGGACGACUUCCUUGGCGUCUACAGCAUGCCGGCGGGGACAAAAGUGUUCGAGGUGCCUGAGAUGUCUCCAGUCACGUGCUGUGACGUCUCUUCCAACAACCGCCUCGUUGUCACAGGCUCCGGGGAGCACGCCUCCGUGUACCAGAUCACCUACUGAGGGGCCUCGCUGCUGUCAUCCCACUCCGGCUCCUCUUUUCAUCCCCCCCCUUCCCCCCCCCCAACAAGGGGGACAUGGUGGAGGGAAGCGGGAAGGCUCUUCUGUGGCAUCGCACGAUCUAGUCUGUGGUGUAGACUGGUCGCCAUCACGUGUAAUAAAGCACCCGGGAAAGGCA